GAUUAGGCCUGGUUUGCGCUGGAGAGUGGUCUUGGUUGUGAGGGUCAUAAGAUGGGAACUCUCCCGGCACGUAGACAUAUCCCGCCGUGGGUGAAAGUUCCCGAAGACCUGAAAGAUCCAGAGGUGUUCCAGGUCCAGACGCGGCUGCUGAAAGCCAUUUUCGGCCCGGACGGAUCUCGAAUCCCUUACAUCGAGCAGGUGAGCAAGGCCAUGCUCGAGCUGAAGGCUCUGGAGUCUUCAGACCUCACCGAGGUCGUGGUUUACGGCUCCUAUUUGUACAAGCUCCGGACCAAGUGGAUGCUCCAGUCCAUGGCUGAGUGGCACCGCCAGCGCCAGGAGCGAGGGAUGCUCAAACUUGCCGAAGCCAUGAAUGCCCUCGAACUAGGCCCUUGGAUGAAGUGAACCAGUUUCCAGCCAAUGCAAUGAAGCCGGGUUGCAGAGAUUAGGUUGUGGCCAGAGCUAGAGUGAUUCCUUAAGCUUGUUUUAAAAUCUGCUCCAGCCUAAAGAGUUAAGGGAAAACCAUUUGUUCCCUUAAAGAGUUAAGGGAAAACCCUUGGCUCUGAGUCUUGUUGUGAAUAUUUCUUUGAUGAUUGUUAAUAAAAAGUGUUUUUUCUUUUUUCCCAUUUUUAAAAAUAACAAUAAAGUUUUAAAUAAGUUGA